GAGGCGGCGGCAGCGGCGGAAGCGGCGAGGGCGGCGGGCGUCCGGCUCUGAGGUGGUGGAGGCGGCGGAGGCGGCGGCGGAGGCGGCGGCGGCUCGGGACUGGGCUCGGCUGGAAGCAGCGAGGGUCAGAGCGCCGCAGCAAGCGCCGAUCUCCCGGCUCGACCAUCCGCCUGCCGCCCGGACGCCUGGGCCGCGGAGUUUGUGUCCCGGCUCGGACCCCGGCGCCCAGCCCGGAGCCGUAACCUUGAGGCGGCGGCGGCGGGGCCGGGCCGGGCCGGGCUGGGGGGCGGUGGCGCUGGAUCCGCGGCUGCCCGAUCGUUGGCGGGAGAUGUCGAACCCCGGGACACGCAGGAACGGCUCCAGCAUCAAGAUCCGUCUGACAG